CUUUCUCUCGCCGCGCCGUCUUGAAGCCGCGCGGGCUCGUGAGCAGCGCGAGGCCGCCAAGGUGCCUCGCUUCGCCGGAGCCGCUGCCGCCCGCCGGAGGGAAGCCGGCCUCGGGCGCGCACGCUCGUCGGAGCCCCGGCGCGCCCCGCGCCUGAGCCUGCUGACAGCGGCCGCUGGGCUCAGGCUGUCCGCUCUGGGCUCCGCGGCCUCGGCCCCGCUGCACUCCACCUCCGCCCCCUCGGACUCCCUCCCCUCUGCUUCUACUCCUCCUGCUCCAGUGCGGAUCGUUUCGCAACUGCUUGCCACUCGUCCCGUGCCUGGCUGUUUUUCCAUUUCCCGGCCCCCUCUUCUUGAGUACUUUACCCCCUGCAUUUGGGGACAGGGACUGGAAAAGGGGCGGGUGGAGCGUCCAGUGGAGAAGAAGGAAGCGAGGCCCGCAGGAGGAGGAGGAUCGGCGGACUGUGGGGAGGAGACCCCACGCCACCCUUUCUGGUCAUCUCCCCUCCCGCCCCGCCCCUGCGCACACUCCCUCGCGGGCGAGCUACUUUCGGACCAGGAAAGUAAGAGCGGCCCUGGGUGACAGCGCCGCGGGGCCAGUCCCGGGGUUAGCCGCGCGUCUGCUCGCUUCUGGUCCGUCGCGCUCCCAGCCAGGGCACAGCCCGGACCGAGGAUGGCUUCGACCACAACCUGCACCAGGUUCACGGACGAGUAUCAGCUUUUCGAGGAGCUUGGAAAGGGGGCAUUCUCAGUGGUGAGAAGAUGUAUGAAAAUUCCUACUGGACAAGAAUAUGCUGCCAAAAUUAUCAACACCAAAAAGCUUUCUGCUAGGGAUCAUCAGAAACUAGAAAGAGAAGCUAGAAUCUGCCGUCUUUUGAAGCACCCUAAUAUUGUGCGACUUCAUGAUAGCAUAUCAGAAGAGGGCUUUCACUACUUGGUGUUUGAUUUAGUUACUGGAGGUGAACUGUUUGAAGACAUAGUGGCAAGAGAAUACUACAGUGAAGCUGAUGCCAGUCAUUGCAUUCAGCAGAUCCUGGAGGCUGUGCUACACUGCCAUCAGAUGGGCGUGGUCCAUCGGGACCUGAAGCCUGAGAAUUUGCUUUUAGCUAGCAAAUCCAAGGGAGCAGCUGUGAAAUUGGCAGACUUUGGCUUAGCCAUAGAAGUUCAAGGGGACCAGCAGGCGUGGUUUGGUUUUGCUGGCACACCUGGAUAUCUUUCUCCAGAAGUUUUACGUAAAGAUCCUUAUGGAAAGCCAGUGGAUAUGUGGGCAUGUGGUGUCAUUCUCUAUAUUCUACUUGUGGGGUAUCCACCCUUCUGGGAUGAAGACCAACACAGACUCUAUCAGCAGAUCAAGGCUGGAGCUUAUGAUUUUCCAUCACCAGAAUGGGACACGGUGACUCCUGAAGCCAAAGACCUCAUCAAUAAAAUGCUUACUAUCAACCCUGCCAAACGCAUCACAGCCUCAGAGGCACUGAAGCACCCAUGGAUCUGUCAACGUUCUACUGUUGCUUCCAUGAUGCACAGACAGGAGACUGUAGACUGCUUGAAGAAAUUUAAUGCUAGAAGAAAACUAAAGGGUGCCAUCUUGACAACUAUGCUGGCUACAAGGAAUUUCUCAGCAGCCAAGAGUUUGUUGAAGAAACCAGAUGGAGUAAAGAUAAACAACAAAGCCAACGUGGUAACCAGCCCCAAAGAAAAUAUUCCUACCCCAGCGCUGGAGCCCCAAACUACUGUAAUCCACAACCCUGAUGGAAACAAGGAGUCAACUGAGAGUUCAAAUACAACAAUUGAGGAUGAAGAUGUGAAAGCACGAAAGCAAGAGAUUAUCAAAGUCACUGAACAACUGAUCGAAGCUAUCAACAAUGGGGACUUUGAAGCCUACACAAAAAUCUGUGACCCAGGCCUUACUGCUUUUGAACCUGAAGCUUUGGGUAAUUUAGUGGAAGGGAUGGAUUUUCACCGAUUCUACUUUGAAAAUGCUUUGUCCAAAAGCAAUAAACCAAUCCACACUAUUAUUCUAAACCCUCAUGUACAUCUGGUAGGGGAUGAUGCCGCCUGCAUAGCAUAUAUUAGGCUCACACAGUACAUGGAUGGCAGUGGAAUGCCAAAGACAAUGCAGUCAGAAGAGACUCGUGUGUGGCACCGCCGGGAUGGAAAGUGGCAGAAUGUUCAUUUUCAUCGCUCGGGGUCACCAACAGUACCCAUCAAGCCACCCUGUAUUCCAAAUGGGAAAGAAAACUUCUCAGGAGGCACCUCUUUGUGGCAAAACAUCUAAGGCCUGAAAACCAUUCACAUAUGGGUCUUCUAAAUUUCAACAGUGCCACUUCUGCAUUCUCUGUUCUCAAGGCACCUGGAUGGUGACCCUGGGCCGUCCUCUCCUCCUCUUCAUGCAUGUUUCUGAGUGCAUGAAGUUGUGAAGGUCCUACAUGUAAUGCAUAUGUGAUGCAUCAUCUUAUCAUAUAUUCCUUCCUAUACAUUGUUUACACUUCAACUACGGGGAUGUUCCACACAAACUUAAAUUACUGUUGGCAAAACAAUAGGGGGAGAUUAGACAAAAAAAAAAAUCCACAAUAUUCCAAGUACAACUCUUCAUCAAGUUUCUCUGUUAAUGCCAAGAUUUAACAGACUUAAGAACUAUUGUUCUCUGAAUGACAGUUGUAAGAGAAAUGUAAAUUUUUUAGAACUCUUUGCUGUUAAUCUGUUUUGGUUUGUUUGGUUUUUUUUUUUUUUUUUAAGGUAAAAAAAAAAUACACCUUCAGUUUCCUGGUGUGAUCCUGGUUAAAAUGGAUGAUUUUUCAUUGAAAGUUUUGCUGAUUAACAAUUAAAGUGGGAUGAUAUGUGGGCAAAAUCACUUAUGAAAGUAGAAGCAAGAAUCAGUUGGUUUGCUACCACAUAAAGCCAUGCUGUUUUUGGUCAAACUGUGUAAACUGGAAAAAUUCACAUCAUUUCUGAGUUUAAUCACUUUAGGAUAUAUUCACAUUGUUUUGGUGAAUUUGCUGAAUUGAAUUGUUUUUCUUUCUCAAAUCUGUGAUCUCUUUUCUUUAUCCUGUUUCUUUGUUCCUUUCGUUUGCUUUCUUAUUUUUCUUUUGUUCCAUUCUUUUCUUACUUUUUUCCCUUUUCCUUUUUUGGGGAGGCUGGCUAGUAGUGUGUGAGAAAAGAAUAGAAGUGAAAUUUGCAUAAUGAAUGUAAAAGGGAAAUAAAAGUCUUUUGAAGGUAGCUAUACUAGCACUUUUGAUCAUCUUCAGGGCCCACAAAAAUGUUGUCAAGAUUUUAAAGGUUUAUAAUUCUGCUUAAGCUCUAGUUUGGACUUAGGUAUCCUAACUAUGUUGGAGGUAUUUGCAUUGUUUAAAGUUAGGAUAAAAGCAAGUUCCUCCUGUGACUGCAACGUCUUACUGAUUGGGACAGUUGCCAGGAGGAUACCAACUUGAUAGCAGAGGGGGUUUUAUGCAAACGCACUCACCUCCGCCUUGGGGAAUGAAAGGGUCACUUCUGCAUCAUCACUAGCUAGUUUUCUAGUGUUAGAGAGGCUUACAAAUGUUUGCCAUUCUCAUAAGUGUUUUGAACUUGAUCUUUGUGACUUGUGCUUUUUUAGCUUCUCUCUUGAAUCAGAGUAUCAUUGUCUUCCUCCAAGGAGUUAGAAUUUCCCAGUUUAAAACAAAAAGGGAAAUGUCCUAGGUUUUCUUUGUGCUUCUCAUUUUUCCUUUGUUGAUUCAAUUCCUGUGAUUUUUGUUCUCUUCCCUGAAGUGCUUUACAGUGCAUGGAAUCUCCAUCAUUGUUAUUUUAACGAUAGUAAUUCACAGUCCUCAGAAGCCUAUUUUUAAAGCAGAAGCAAAAAAGAAAAACAAAAUAACAAAAACAACCCUUCCUCUUUUCUCUCAUCUCACCUCUCUGUGUUGAUUACUAAUCAUCUUAGAUAUUAUUGCUAGUGGAUGUAUGGUAGAUGGGUUGAAGCUUUUCUGAUAAUUAUUACACAAUUUAAAACAACAUAUAUAUUUAAAAUAAAUAUAUACAGUAAAUAUAUUGAGCCAUGUUAACCUGCCAAUGAGAUCUGUGAAAAAAUAAUGGCCUCAUUUUUCUCUUUUUAAUUUCUUUUACCCUUUUGUGAAGCAGCUAUACGUGGCAUACAUGUAUUUAAAGAAAAAAAAAUAGAUGUAGAGUGUUUUUUUUACACUUUUAACUUAGCAUGUGGUGUUGAAGUAUUACUGUAGAUCAAGUUUGUCUUCCGCACUAAGAUGUGAGGAAAUUGUGAUUUGUUCUCUCCACCACAAAUGAAUUACACAUUUAUUAUCUUCUAUCAUUUUGAAACACUGCAGUUUACCAUGGGACACUGUAUAUAUUUCUUGCCAUAAUGGUAAAGGACUGAUUGAUAUAUUUAAGAGUUAAUAAAUUUGUGAUUUCUGCUGACAGUGCGUCCAUCUUUAUUUCUUCAGAAGAGGUACUGUAUGUAUGCCUGCAUAGUGCUGGCCAGUGUCAAGGGCAGUGUGUCCUACUCUGGUCUCAUUUAGUACAUAACAAUUUGCACUUGGUGAGAAUGGCAAGUUAAUUGUUCUCUGUGAGCAAAACAAUGGUCUCUUCUGGGAAAAUGUUGCUGAGAACAAUAUAGUUAACAACUAAGACUCCUAAAAGCUUCUCUAAACUGUACCCUCCAAUCCAGCCUUCACAUGGCUGCUUUUUUUUUUUUUUUUUAAUACGAACCUGUCCUUGUAACACUUUGAUGUUAUCAUUUCUGGGAUACAGGCAAGCACCCCAGCUCCUGCUACUCCCCAGCUUGAACUUGAGCAUACAUGGAUGCUCAGCUUCUUUUGAUUUGCUAAAAACAUCACACUUGCUCACAUGCCUGUUUAUGCUGUUCAUGUUGUUUAUGUUUCUUACCUAGAAUAAAUAGUCUCUUCCCCUACUUCUUUUCCCGACUUCUUACUUUUUCCUAAGAUUCAGUGUACAGCAUCAUGCUCCACAGCAAACCUUCCUAGGCCCUAUUCUGGGCUUGCCUUCCCUCUCAAAACCUACAUAAUAGAUUGUAUUUACCUCUCCUGUCAACCACAUUGUUUUGAAAAUAUAUUUCUAUUUGUGUCUCCUCUACUGCAGUAUAAUGUCUCCAUGGGCAAGAACUGUGUAUUCAUCAUUGCAUUCCUAAACCCAAACCAAGGCCAGGAAUGGAGAUAUCAUUGAUAAAUAGUUGUUGAAUUGAGGCCAAGCCCUUUUGAUAACAGAAGCCUCAAGGGGUACCCAGAUAGUCCUUGUUUUAAUGAUGGGUUCUCUCACCACUGUCUUGAUGCUCUGAGCAAGUUACCUCUUCCCUCUGACCCUCAGUUUCCAUAUUUGUAAAAUGAGAAUAAACAUACCAACUUAAUAAAGAUAUUGUGAGGAUUAAUGGGUACAGAGUGACUAGAAUGAUAUUUGAUAGAAAUUAAAUGGUAGCAGUAUAACUAUUCUGAUCACUGACAUUAAUAUUCCUAUUGUUAUUAUUCUUUGCUCACGAGGGUAUACAACUCUUGUUUUGCUGUUGGGCUGCCCUCUUUAUGUAGGUUUACUGUUAAUGCUGAGGAUAUACUCGGACUCAAAUGUCUCAGCAGAAGGCUGAGAGACACCAAAUGAAGUGGUCAUCUAGCUGAAUGUAGGAAAAAUGAAAUGUAGUAGCAAAUCAGUAUAUUCUAAGGAAAUUUUCAAGGAAUAUUAAUCUUCACCCAAAUUUUGAAUUUUUAUGUAAAAAAUUAUAAUUUAAGGGUAAACAUAGAUGACACAGCUUUCGAGUGAUUUCAUUGAAUAAAAUUCUACUGACUUCUAUGAA